GAGUGACCCGGCGUGGCUACUAGGAGAAGGACGUACGGUCCUGCUAGUAGAGGAAUAUGUCGAGUUUCUCUAGGGCGCCCCAGCAAUGGGCCACUUUUGCUAGAAUAUGGUAUCUCUUAGAUGGGAAAAUGCAGCCACCUGGCAAACUUGCUGCUAUGGCAUCUAUAAGACUUCAGGGAUUACAUAAACCUGUGUACCAUGCACUGAGUGACUGUGGGGAUCAUGUUGUUAUAAUGAACACAAGACACAUUGCAUUUUCUGGAAACAAAUGGGAACAAAAAGUAUACUCUUCGCAUACUGGCUACCCAGGUGGAUUUAGACAAGUAACAGCUGCUCAGCUUCACCUGAGGGAUCCAGUGGCAAUUGUAAAACUAGCUAUUUAUGGCAUGCUGCCAAAAAACCUUCACAGAAGAACAAUGAUGGAAAGGUUGCAUCUUUUUCCAGAUGAGUAUAUUCCAGAAGAUAUUCUUAAGAAUUUAGUAGAGGAGCUUCCUCAACCACGAAAAAUACCUAAACGUCUAGAUGAGUACACACAAGAAGAAAUAGACGCCUUCCCAAGAUUGUGGACUCCACCUGAAGAUUAUCGGCUAUAAGAGAAUAAGAAUUGCAGAAAAUAACAGUGAAGUGAUUGAAACUUUCUUCUGAUGAGUUUCUCUAACCUACAGGAUGGAGUAAAACAACUGCUACAGUUCAGCACCUGUUUUAUGUGCCGAAUCACUGUGGGGAAAGGUCAGGAAGGUAUAGUCCUUCAAUAGGAAAUUGUAAUUAAAAUAUAAUUUUAUAGAACCAUUUUUAUGUAAUCUGAUUUGAAUGUUAUAGUUGAUAAUAAUAAAAUCACUUACUUGGUUGACUAUUUAGUGUUGCAUUUAAUGAUAAAAAACAGACCCUGUGUAUAGAAUUGCAGUUACACAUUCCAAAAAUGCCUCUCCAUGCAGAUUUUCUCAAGUUUGCAGGUCACUAUUCUUGUCCCUUGUGAACAAGCUCUACCUUCACUUUUCAUUUCAGUGGCUUUUUUUAUCUAACUUGUCAUCCAUCUAAAUUCAUAUUUGCAGCUUAGUAGGGUAAAGUUUGCCCUGAAAUAUUUAUAAACUGCUAUCUUUUUCUGUGUCCCAUAUAGCCUCUUGGCCCCACAAUGACACCAGAAUACAUAAUGCCUGUCUGCUCGUUAGAAAUCCCUCUUCCCUGCCAGUGAUUCUGUUUGUAGACUCUCCACACUGUUUUCCCAUAUCUGUCCUGUUGGCUUCCAUUCAUCUCUGUACU